GGAUAAAGUCCUCCACUGUGGGUGGUGGAAGAGGCUUCUUCUACCUCCUCCCCAUAGUUCCUGAAGGCACCAAGACUGUCACAGUAAUUGUUAUAUUAUGAAAAGAGUAAAUUGAAGAAAUGGAAACUGCAAAUUACACCAAGGUGACAGAAUUUGUUCUCACUGGCCUAUCCCAGACUCGGGAGGUCCAACUAGUCCUAUUUGUUAUAUUUCUAUCCUUCUAUUUGUUCAUCCUACCAGGAAAUAUCCUUAUCAUUUGCACCAUCAGGCUAGACCCUCAUCUGACUUCUCCUAUGUAUUUCCUGUUGGCUAAUCUGGCCCUCCUUGAUAUUUGGUACUCUUCCAUUACAGCCCCUAAAAUGCUCAUAGACUUCUUUGUGGAGAGGAAGAUAAUUUCCUUUGGUGGAUGCAUUGCACAGCUCUUCUUCUUACACUUUGUUGGGGCUUCGGAGAUGUUCUUGCUCACAGUGAUGGCCUAUGACCGCUAUGCUGCUAUCUGCCGACCCCUCCACUAUGCUACCAUCAUGAAUCGACGUCUCUGCUGUAUCCUGGUGGCUCUCUCCUGGAUGGGGGGCUUCAUUCAUUCUAUAAUACAGGUGGCUCUCAUUGUUCGACUUCCUUUCUGUGGGCCCAAUGAGUUAGACAGUUACUUCUGUGACAUCACACAGGUUGUCCGGAUUGCCUGUGCCAACACCUUCCCAGAGGAGUUAGUGAUGAUCUGUAGUAGUGGUCUGAUCUCUGUGGUGUGUUUCAUUGCUCUGUUAAUGUCCUAUGCCUUCCUUCUGGCCUUGCUCAAGAAACAUUCAGGCUCAGGUGAGAAUACCAACAGGGCCAUGUCCACCUGCUAUUCCCACAUUACCAUUGUGGUGCUAAUGUUUGGGCCAUCCAUCUACAUUUAUGCUCGCCCAUUUGACUCAUUUUCCCUAGAUAAAGUGGUGUCUGUGUUUCAUACUGUAAUAUUCCCUUUACUUAAUCCCAUUAUUUACACAUUGAGAAACAAGGAAGUAAAGGCAGCCAUGAGGAAGGUGGUCACCAAAUAUAUUUUGUGUGAAGAGAAGUGAAAGAUAAAUUAUACAUUUUAUAGUCCUCCUGAGGAUCAUUGUCCUAAAGCAGGAAGUAUUUGCAGUAAUAAUGCUGCAUUCACUUCCUCCGUUCAUUUGUGUUCUUAAAAUUUUACUAUAAUUUUUCUCUAUUAAUUCCUCUUUAUAUUGAAAAAAUAGAGGCAUUAAGAUGAAAAUAAAUUUACUCACACCUACCCUGAAAUUCCAGGCAGAUCAUUAUUAGAAUUUGAGAUAUAAUAAUAAUCUGCUAAAGUACAUUUUAACUAAUUGUUUAUUGAGUAACUACUCUGCAGAGGCUCUGGCUUUGAGGGGAACAUGUUGAUAAAAAUAAAUAAGACAUGGAGACGUGUCCAUUACAAAUAUGAAGUAAAUGGCAAGCAUAUGGAUGCAGCUAGCUUCAAGUUAGCAAAUAAAUAUUGUCAAGUUUCAGUGUUGGCUCAGUGGAAUGGUAUCUGGUAAACAUCUUGCUGGGUCUGGAAAAACAGAUUAUUUGUCCUUUAUCUCCUCUUAUUUCCAGAGUUGAUGGAAAAUGAGGAUUCAUUUAUAGAAGGUAUUUCAGUUUAUAUUUCAGGUGGUGUCCAUUCAACAGUUGGAGACAGAACUCAAAAUUUUAUCACAUUAUGAAAACAAAUUUUAUGAAUUCAAAGCAGAGUAUAAUUUGGCUGAUACAUGAGAUUCAUGUCAUUCCAGAUGAAGCCUCCAGGCAACUAGCAAUUUUUAUAGCCAGUCCCUACUUACAUCCUUCAGAGUGAAAGCAGGCUUGGGGAGAAAGCUUCUAGGUUGACUGGAAUUGGUAGACAUCUAGCCGUGUAGUUUUUUUCUAAACUAUCAUCUCCUUUGCCACUUUUGUAUGUUUUCCGUAAUUGCUAAUCCUGCCUCUCAUGUUAAACUUAAAUUGGUUAGGUGCUGUUUUUGUUAGCGCUUAAUUCAGAGUUAUUUCCCAUUGAGAGACCUGGAUGUGUUGGUUCCCAUGAUCCCUUAGAGAAUUAUUAGGGACUGAUUUCCUAUUUUCAAGCACUAAAAACUCACUCUCCAAGCUUCUGAAUGUAAGAGGUAGAUUAGAACAUUUGAUUUUAUAGGUUAUGUUUUUUACUUAAAUUUAUUAGUUUUUCAUUUCAAAACUAGGAAAUAUUUUCAUUGAAGGGCAAGAAUGCAUUGGGUGUAUUAAGCUUUAGUCUUCUUUUUUAAAUUUGAUAAUGUAAUAUGGACUAAAUUUUAAGUGAAUUAGAUCCUUGUCAACAUUAGGAAUGAAUAUAUAAAAAUAAAUCGUAUAACUAUUCCUAGAGUUACUAUUUAUUUACAGAGAUUUAUUUAUUAAUUGAGGAGGUAAUUUAUGCCAGACCCAGUGUACCUCGGAUGCACAGGAUGGAAUGGUGGUACACAAAGCUUGUUUUUUGCUUUGGGAAUUUUUCCUUAUGGUGACCUUCUUCGAUCUUCAAUGCUACGUUACUUCUCUUCUAGGAACCCAAAGGCAUGGAUUGAUGUUAUGAGUCCUGAUUUUUGAGUUGACUUCUCAUCACCUGGAAGUGAAUAAAGCAGUAGACUUCUCUAACAUUUUGUAACACAGCAUGAAAAAAUAUAAAGUACAAAAGAUAUAUAUAUAUAAUAUGAUAAAAUGAUGAGUUAUGUUUCUAAAUCUUUUAUCAUCUUACUGUCAUUUCUCUGUAUUUGAUCUAGCCAGACUUCUAUUCAUUUUGUCACUUAUCUUUCAUCAAACUAGGGCUGAUGUUCUUUGGAAAGGGACCACUGAUUUGAUAUGCUCUUCAAACACCAGCACACUGUACUACAGAAGGAUAUUUACUGAAAAUACUGAAGCUAGUAAUACAAAGGAAAAAGGCAUAAAAACAGUAGUGUGAUAACUAAUUGCUUACUUGGGAAUAUUAUCUGAAAUUAGAAACUAAUAUCAAUGAAGAAAAAGGGGAACUUUUGGCAAACUCUAGUAAGUAAUAACUGAGCCUGAUUCAUGGAGGACAUAAUUGGAAUAAGGACUGAGAGCAAUUUCACCCCUUGGAGGACAUUUGGAAGUGCCCAGAGACAUUUGUGGUGGUCACAACUGAGGACGUAUAUUGGCAUCUUGUACUAUUUAGACAUCUUACAAUGCACAGGACAGCCCCCAGCCCCUGACUCCCACAUGAAUUAUCUGGCCCAAAAUGUCAAUAGUGCCGAGAAUGAAGAACUCCAUCAGGUUGAGAAACUCUGACUUAAAUAAUGGGCAGGGAUAAGGCAGGUUAGUGUAGAAGAAAUAGGUGUUAACCUCAUAUGCAAUGUUGUGUCAUUGAAUAUUGUUUCCAAAUAGCUCAGUAUCCUCAGCAAUCACAUACAAAAUAUGCCUCAGGACUCCUUUUCCCUAUAUAACUCCUACAUUUUCUUUCAGUUACUUUUAAAUGUCUUUUAAUCUCUUUUUUUCUUUCAGUCUCUCCUAGUCCUCCUUC